GCACUUGUACAUUUCUGCAGCCGCGCGGCGAGCCAUUCGCGGCGGCUGCUGCAGCUCCUACUGCAUCUUCCUUCUCUUCCUUUCCUCGGGCUCCGGUCUCGGAGUCGGAGAGCGCGCCUCGCUUCCAGAGCCCCCGGACCCGGCGAGUCAGCGAUCGCCGAGCCGGCCACCAUGCCCGGCAGACCGCGCCACUAGGCGCUCCUCGCGGCUCCCACCCGGCGGCGGCGGCGGCGGCGGCGGCGUCCGCGAUGGUUUCAGACGCUGAAGGAUUUUGCAUCUGAUCGCUCGGCGUUUCAAAGGCAGAGGCCCCCCCUCCCCCUUCCCCCCUCCCUCGCCGUCUUUGUUUCCUUCCCCCCCUGCUCUCCCCACUCCCCCCACCCCACCCCCCUCUCCUCUCCUCCUCCUCUUUUUUAGAAGCAGCGAUCGGAGAUGGAUGUCUCUCUUUGCCCAGCCAAGUGUAGUUUCUGGCGGAUUUUCUUGCUGGGAAGCGUCUGGCUGGACUAUGUGGGCUCCGUGCUGGCUUGCCCUGCAAAUUGUGUCUGCAGCAAGACUGAGAUCAAUUGCCGGCGGCCGGACGAUGGGAACCUCUUCCCCCUCCUGGAAGGGCAGGAUUCAGGGAACAGCAAUGGGAACGCCAGUAUCAACAUCACGGACAUCUCAAGGAAUAUCACUUCCAUACACAUAGAGAACUGGCGCAGUCUUCACACGCUCAACGCCGUGGACAUGGAGCUCUACACCGGACUUCAAAAGCUGACCAUCAAGAACUCAGGACUUCGGAGCAUUCAGCCCAGAGCCUUUGCCAAGAACCCCCAUUUGCGUUAUAUAAACCUGUCAAGUAACCGGCUCACCACACUCUCGUGGCAGCUCUUCCAGACGCUGAGUCUUCGGGAAUUGCAGUUGGAGCAGAACUUUUUCAACUGCAGCUGUGACAUCCGCUGGAUGCAGCUCUGGCAGGAGCAGGGGGAGGCCAAGCUCAACAGCCAGAACCUCUACUGCAUCAACGCUGAUGGCUCCCAGCUUCCUCUCUUCCGCAUGAACAUCAGUCAGUGUGACCUUCCUGAGAUCAGCGUGAGCCACGUCAACCUGACCGUACGAGAGGGUGACAACGCUGUUAUCACUUGCAAUGGCUCUGGAUCACCCCUUCCUGAUGUGGACUGGAUAGUCACUGGGCUGCAGUCCAUCAACACUCACCAGACCAAUCUGAACUGGACCAAUGUUCAUGCCAUCAACUUGACGCUGGUGAAUGUGACGAGUGAGGACAAUGGCUUCACCCUGACGUGCAUUGCAGAGAACGUGGUGGGCAUGAGCAAUGCCAGUGUUGCCCUCACUGUCUACUAUCCCCCACGUGUGGUGAGCCUGGAGGAGCCUGAGCUGCGCCUGGAGCACUGCAUCGAGUUUGUGGUGCGUGGCAACCCCCCACCAACGCUGCACUGGCUGCACAAUGGGCAGCCUCUGCGGGAGUCCAAGAUCAUCCAUGUGGAAUACUACCAAGAGGGAGAGAUUUCCGAGGGCUGCCUGCUCUUCAACAAGCCCACCCACUACAACAAUGGCAACUAUACCCUCAUUGCCAAAAACCCACUGGGCACAGCCAACCAGACCAUCAAUGGCCACUUCCUCAAGGAGCCCUUUCCAGAGAGCACGGAUAACUUUAUCUUGUUUGACGAAGUGAGUCCCACACCUCCUAUCACUGUGACCCACAAACCAGAAGAAGACACUUUUGGGGUAUCCAUAGCAGUUGGACUUGCUGCUUUUGCCUGUGUCCUGUUGGUGGUUCUCUUCGUCAUGAUCAACAAAUAUGGUCGACGGUCCAAAUUUGGAAUGAAGGGUCCCGUGGCUGUCAUCAGUGGUGAGGAGGACUCAGCCAGCCCACUGCACCACAUCAACCACGGCAUCACCACGCCCUCGUCACUGGAUGCCGGGCCCGACACUGUGGUCAUUGGCAUGACUCGCAUCCCUGUCAUUGAGAACCCCCAGUACUUCCGUCAGGGACACAACUGCCACAAGCCGGACACGUAUGUGCAGCACAUUAAGAGGAGAGACAUCGUGCUGAAGCGAGAACUGGGUGAGGGAGCCUUUGGAAAGGUCUUCCUGGCCGAGUGCUACAACCUCAGCCCGACCAAGGACAAGAUGCUUGUGGCUGUGAAGGCCCUGAAGGAUCCCACCCUGGCUGCCCGGAAGGAUUUCCAGAGGGAGGCCGAGCUGCUCACCAACCUGCAGCAUGAGCACAUUGUCAAGUUCUAUGGAGUGUGCGGCGAUGGGGACCCCCUCAUCAUGGUCUUUGAAUACAUGAAGCAUGGAGACCUGAAUAAGUUCCUCAGGGCCCAUGGGCCAGAUGCAAUGAUCCUUGUGGAUGGACAGCCACGCCAGGCCAAGGGUGAGCUGGGGCUCUCCCAAAUGCUCCACAUUGCCAGUCAGAUCGCCUCGGGUAUGGUGUACCUGGCCUCCCAGCACUUUGUGCACCGAGACCUGGCCACCAGGAACUGCCUGGUUGGAGCGAAUCUGCUAGUGAAGAUUGGGGACUUCGGCAUGUCCAGAGAUGUCUACAGCACGGAUUAUUACAGGGUGGGAGGACACACCAUGCUCCCCAUUCGCUGGAUGCCUCCUGAAAGCAUCAUGUACCGGAAGUUCACUACAGAGAGUGAUGUAUGGAGCUUCGGGGUGAUCCUCUGGGAGAUCUUCACCUAUGGAAAGCAGCCAUGGUUCCAACUCUCAAACACGGAGGUCAUUGAGUGCAUUACCCAAGGUCGUGUUUUGGAGCGGCCCCGAGUCUGCCCCAAAGAGGUGUACGAUGUCAUGCUGGGGUGCUGGCAGAGGGAACCACAGCAGCGGUUGAACAUCAAGGAGAUCUACAAAAUCCUCCAUGCUUUGGGGAAGGCCACCCCAAUCUACCUGGACAUUCUUGGCUAGUGGUGGCUGGUGGUCAUGAAUUCAUACUCUGUUGCCUCCUCUCUCCCUGCCUCACAUCUCCCUUCCACCUCACAACUCCUUCCAUCCUUGACUGAAGCGAACAUCUUCAUAUAAACUCAAGUGCCUGCUACACAUACAACACUGAAAAAAGGAAAAAAAAAGAAAGAAAAAAAAACCCUGUAAGGCAGUUUGGCAAAUAUAUAUAUAUAUAUAUAUAUUUAUAUAUCUAACUAUCUAUCAAUCUAUAUCUACAGAGAGUUACCUUCUCUAGUACACAGAGAAGCUGCUGAUACAGAAAACCACAAGACUUUAACAACUCAGAAACUCUAAAAUAUUAAUAAUACAAAGGAAAAUUCCCUUUGACUUAAGCUGUGGCCCAUGCUUCUAAUGCUACGGCUCUUUGGAGCAGAAGACCUGGACCAUGCAGAGAGACAAUCUUUGGGAUGAGAGCUCUGGGACGGGAGGAGUUAAGGUGGUGCUCAGUCGCUGCUGUGUGUGUCUGUUACCCCGGAAGCUCACCACAGGCACAUGUGGGGACUGCAUGGCUGUGCUCAGCAAAGAAAUGAUGCCUGAGCAGGGUCCUUGCCUCCACUUCUUCCCCAUUUCCUCCACUUCAGGACAAUGUUCUAAUUUGUCCAUUCUAAAAAGUGUAAUCUUGAUGCUUUUGGGAAUCAAUGAUGGCACCUACGGGUAAACACAGAACAGACAACCCCACAACACAAAACCAUGACAAGAGCUGACAGCAUCCAUCCUGGGUGUAAGCUUCUUGCUGGAGUUGCAAAGGAUGUGUCUUUCUAUUCUCAGAACUUAAAGAACUGGACUUUCUGGAGUAAAAGAACCACAGAAGAAAAAAUAGCUGAAACCUGAACCCUGCCAAGACACUGCCACCUGUCUUUUCCAUCAUUGCAAAGAUUCCUUGGCCUCACCUCCCACUUUCAGGCCCCUGGGAAGCUUAGGGGGUUAGGAAACAGGUCCCCAUGUUAUCUUUGAAUGUAGACACAGCACGCUUUAGGGUUGCAAUAGCAAGAGACUUGGUUGCUUGUAGGUCAUUAUAACGAAUGCCCCCUGGUCCUCUCAGUUUCUCAUCCUGCUUCCCUAGAUCCUAGACCCCACUUCCUGGGUCUCUACUGAGUCCCAGGUAAACCCCACUGCCAAGGAAGGGAGCCAGGUCUAGUGAGAGGCUGCAGCAGUGAGUGUUUCAGGAAAGCAAGCAGUGGAGUGGGUGAGAGCCAGCAGGGGAGAAUCUACUUGGCACCUGUGCCAGGCCCCUUGGCAUUCUCCUCACGUUUCCAGCCCCUGGGAGGAUUGAUGCAUCUGCCUUUGAGCUGUUGUGAAAACGCAGGGGCUGAGAAAUCACUUUUGUGGGCUGGGGUAGGGGGAAGGGCUGAGGCUUCUCUGGGAGAUGUCCAAUGAGCGGCCAGUGCUGCAGGCUUGGAAUCUUAAUGAGGCCUGAGCCCUGACCGGAGAGAGGGAAGGAAACAUCUGUGCUGGGGCCUGCUCCCUCUGCCCCAGCACUGGGGAAUCACUGCCUUCCUGGCUGCUGCCACAUACCACAGUGGGGCCGACCUCUGGGCCUCCCUGUCACAUGAAACAUGGAAGCCAACAGCCUGGCCCCACAGAUCUCCUCUGCUGGAGAGGAGAGGAUGUGUUCCUCCCAGGCCACGGGGCCCCUCUGCCUUGCCCCAAGCACAGAGCUACCUAAGGGACUGACCUUUGCCACACUGGAGCUCACCUCCCGGGGGCCUCUGGCCUACCCUUUUCCCUGCCAGCUGAAGAGACUGCCGGCAGCCUGGACGUCCUGGUUAGCUGAAGGCAGCUGAAAUGUGGGCCUCCCUAUGUGGGGUUUAGUACUGAAUUAUGUGUUUGUGGUUUUGCUUCUUUUUGUAGACCCACAAAUAUUUUUAUUUGAAUAGUAAAGAGCUGUGCUCAGAUUGUAGCCAUGGUUGGGAUUUGGGAUCAACGAGGCUGGUUAGCUGGACUGGGAGGGGAGGCAGGUGAGAUGGGAAUUUGGUGUUGGUUUUCUCACUGUGCUGUGCUCCUAGCCCCUGAGGACUUUGCAGGAAAGCUGUUUGGAUUGACCACCUCAAGGAACUCCUUUGCUGUCCUAUGACAAUUACUCCUCUUGUCUUUCCACCUAGAGGACCGUUAUGCCGGGGCUGUGAGUUCUGGCUGAAGCUGCACAAUCUGGCUUUGAUCUGGGUAGCUAAGAACAGGUGUUCAGGGAGGGCAUGGUCUGGAGGCGCCUGAGGGAAAAGUAUCUUCUGGUUAGAAGUGAAGCACCAAUGCUCCUGUUGCUUCCCUUCUCCCAUAUCCUCUCCUGAACAAACACUGUGUGGCUUCUGUCUUCUUGGCUGUGUGUUUCAAAACUGAUAGUCACUGAUGGGCUGGGAAGAAGCAGGAGAAGAACUGGGUUGGAGAUGGGUGGAAAACUGGGAAUAAGGACCAUGCUAUGGUUUUAUCUUCAGGGCACUGAUUCAUCAUGGCCUAAUGAAAGAAGGUGAUUCCUUGGGGGAACAAGAAGCACUGAAGGAGACCGCAGUUGUCAGAUUGCUGCCACCUUAGGCCCACGGGCUUUCACGCUGAUCUUGGGGUCAUGUUCUUACUGUGUCCAUUGUAAGCAGCUGGCUGUGGAAGAGUGCCAGAGAGAGAGGGGCAGAGCAGGGAAGGGUAGCGAGGGAAGAUAUAUUACUUUGAUAUAUUAGCCUUGGCAGAUUAAAAAAAAAAGAUUUAUUUUGGAGAGUAAAGGAGGCAGAAAAUAGGGCCAUGGAAAUUGCAGGGUACACUAUGGCUCUGGGGAGUGUGGCAUGUACUGGGACACACCUGUCCCUCCUAUAUUGGGACAGGACUGAUAAGGCUUAGUACACUGUAUCUUAAUUUCCCCAUCUGCAGAAUAAGGGGUACACCUGCUAAUCUCUGGCCCCUUCUAGCUCUGAGUUCUUAGAUUCUGACAACGUUGUGUCACUGUGCCAUUUUUCUCAAUACCAUUCUGGAAUGGCAGGACAGCCUUGCAUAGGUGGGGGGCAGUUGCCGCUGAAGGCUCACUGGGCCUGGGCAAGGCUGAGUUCCAAUAAGACACUCCUCUCCUUCUUUGCCCCUUGUCUCAACAUUUCGGAGUCUGAAGUGUCUGAGACGACUGUAAGCCAGGAGGGGAGCAUUUGGUCGGCUUCCCAUCCUGGCAUUCCUACAUACCAGAAAAGCACUGUCGACGGUCCAUUUAUUUAUUUAUUUAUGAAGAGCCUAAUGUGAUGAAAUGUGUUGUGAAAUGACAUCCUAUUAGCCAAUAUGGCCACUCCAGUUCAUUUCACCCUCAUUUUCCCAUACCAAAGUCCACCUUUUAGAAGACCAUGUCACAUCGCCUCUGAGAGCUUAGCUUUGAAGUGAGCUCUUUUGUGUCUUUUGAUGAACGCUCCAGGGCACCCAGGCUGGUCUCUCUGCCAUGCCAACCUCACCGGAUCCUCUCCUGGACUGAGUGAGAGUGACCUGCUGUUGGGUGUCCACCUUGGAGUAGGGUGUUGUGGCCAUGGGACCUCCCAAUUCUUCUUUCUUUGGAUGUGAACCUAACUCUGCCCUCUAAUGAUAUCCCUGAACUCUGAGGGGACCUUGGGCAUCACUGAACCUCCUCUAGUCAAGAGACAAGAAAAAGGAGGUGCUGCUUCCUCCAUUCAGCAGAUCAUGCACAAAUUACUCCUAGACAGAGGCUUCCCACUUGAGGCAAAGGAUCUUUGGUCCUUCUGGGUUCAGGUUGAACAUUAAUGUUCUUCUCUAGUGAUGCCUACUUUGCGGAAUACACUAGUGCAAGUCAUUUUGGUGCUAAAUACUGCAGAAACCAACACCAACGGGAGAGCUGUCAGCCAGCUUCUGGGGCUGCACGAGACUCAACUCAGAAGUAGAAGUGAGUCAGCCAUGCCGGGAGAGUACAGGGUGCAUUGGAAGUUAAGUAGAAAAGUGGCAGGGUGAAAAGACCAGCAAAAUUUCUGAUUUUGCUAUUAGUUAUCCACGUGGCCUUGGCCAAAUCAGCUUAUUUCUCAUUUGAGACGUUUAAGAGGUUUGUAUAGAUAUUUUUAGAGUCCUUUUCAUUUUUUUAAAGCUAGGUUCUGGUCCCACCUGAUAUAUAUGUACUUGCUUGUUAAAAAUAAGAGAUGAAGUGAAAGAUAAGGAAGGAGACGAAGAAAAGUUACCAAUGGCAAAGGAUUGAUUAUAGAAGACAAUGAAAGAAGGCCUGGUGACUGGUAGAUUUGAGGAAUAUUGUACAGGGAGCCAGGCAGACAAGCCAGAGACUUCAUUUUUAUGCUCUUCACAGGAGGUCACUGGCCUAGCCACUUGCCUGCGUUUCACCAGGCUGUUCCCCUCAGCUAGUCAACCUUCCCUGUUCAAAACCAACAUGCUAACACUUGGCAGAAACUAUUCCAAGAUAUGGAGAGAGGCCUGCCCAUCUCUCAUGCAGGCCACUGGAAAUCAACUCUGGGUCAAAACCGACAAGAUUUUUAUCUUUUAAUGCUUAUUGUAAGAGGCCGGGAUGUUUGAAAGAGGGCAGCGUCUUAAGUUGCAGACUAUUCACCAAAGUCCUUUUCUAUUCAGGAAUGACUAAUGACUUUCUUUGUUCCCCUUUUCCAAACCAAACAGCAGCAGUAUUACCUUGACUCCAAAGUACAGUGAUUGCAAUGGACAGUCUUGAGAUUAAGGGUCUUUUUAGUGCUUUGCUCGGAAUCUGGAGCAAGGAAAUGUCUAGGGAUGUUUGUUGAAUGAACCCACCUGCCAGCAGUCCAGAGAGCUGUCCCAAAGGCCCCUGAGAUGUCUAUUGUCUGCUUUGGUAGGGAGCCAACCUGCUAGAAGACUCAAGGGCAUUUGCCUUAGAGAGAAAAAAAAAUGGCACAUUUAGUUCCGGGCUUGGGUGCUGAAGUCACUGUGUUUUUGGCUCCUGAAGCUCCACUUUCUUUUUUCAUACCAAAUAAAUUGUUUUGGCCAAUAUUUAAGGAUUUAAAUAUUUAAGGUUUUGAAGGAAAAUUCCAAGUUUAUGCAUCAUUAUUAAGACAUCAAUAUGGGCUUGGGAAAAUGUUUUGGUGUUGCUUAAUAAUACUGGGAGUGUCUUCUAAAGAAAGUAUACAUAUAUGUACGUUGUGUGUUUAUUUCUAUAUAUUGGAUUGGAAUGGCUUCAAAGAAGGCCUGUUUGAAGUCAGCAAAUUGAUUUCAAUUUGGGAUUCUCUUUUAGCCUUACCGUUCUUGGGGAUAAGAAAUCUGGAGAUGAACUGGCCUCAGAAACAUUCAGGAAGAUUACGAUGGGAAAUCUGUCAUCUUGUAAAGUUGGAUCAUUUGGUGCUCUCUGAACUAAAUUAUGCUGACUAACAUUCUGAGCAUCUGAAAAUCAUUCUUCCUGGUUGCCUGAUAGAUGACCACACAGGAGUCAUUUCUAUCACAUCUUAUUUGGGGGUUGGUAUAGACGCCACCAGCACUGCAGGGAAAACCACCCCCUAGGAGGGGUGAGACAGAGAGAAUGUGAGAUUUUGAUCAUUGAUUGCUCUUUCUGAAAGGCACUGCUGACCAUAGUAGGUGUGGUGAAUGUUUGUGUCACUGCAUUGGGUAUUAGAACUUUUGCUCUGAGCAUGGGCUGCCCUACCCUGAAGAGCUGAAUCUUGGCUUCUGACAGAAGCUCUGCAUGACUCAUUCUCCUCAAGCAUAUUUUCCUUAUUUUCCUAUGAAAGUAUCUAUAGUUUGCAACAAGAACUGUCUUUGGUUCAAGUGUCAGUGUACUAGAAUAGAUGCUUUUCUGUGAGACCUGUGGAGGUUGGAUUGGGGUGGGGGGUGUUCCUUCAAAGUACUUGGAAUUCUUUAUCAAAGAAAUAAAACUCAGAUUCUCUUCUUUCUAGUUUACUUCUAAGUUCCAAAUUUAAAACAAGACCCAGUUUGACAUUUGCAGUAGGAGAUAAUGUCUUGAACCAGUGAGCUUGGCUAUCUUUCUUUCAUCAUAGGGAGGCAGGGCAGUAAGUUGUAUUAAUUUUUCCUAAUCACCCAGGCAAAUAUUGCUUUUUGUUCAGUGUCGUGACCCACAUUCAUAGCUUGCAGGGGAUACUUCUAGCUGACAAAGCUGGAAGUUUCUAAUAGAAGAUGUAUCAAGAUAACAGAGGUGAGGAAAGGCCUGUUGAACAUCUACUUCUGAGAAUCAUUGAGGCACUCAGGUCUUGCUUUUCAGUUUAGUAUCUUACAAAAGGAGUUGGUUUCUUCUCAUUUUAGCAAUGAUAAAUUUAGACAUCUUUUUUGAAAGGCCAAAGGUAGAUUGAGAGCUCAAAUACUUACGGUGUACUCUGACAGUCUUUUAUUCUAUUUUUCAAGACUUAUUUUAUAUAUACAUAUUUUUUAUUUCCAUAGGUUAUUGGGGAACAGGUAGUGUUUGGUUACAUGAGUAAGUUCUUUGGUGGUGAUUUGUGAGAUUUUGGCACACCCAUCACCCAGGCAGUAUGCACCAUAUUUGUAGUCUUUUAUCCCUCACUCCCUUCCCACACUUUCCCCCUGAGUCCGCAGAGUCCAUUGUGUCAUUCUUAUACCUUGACAUCCUCACAGCUUAGCUCCCACAUAUCAGUGAGAACGUACGAUGUUUGGUUUUCUAUUCCUGAAUUGCUUCACUUAGAAUAGUGGUCUCCAAUCUCACCCAGGCCGCUUCGAAUGCCAUUAAUUCAUUCCUUUUUAUGGAUGAGUAGUAUUCCAUCAUACAUAUAUAUGUUUGUGUGUGUGUGUGUGUGUGUGUGUGUGUGUGUGUGUACCACAGUUUCUUUAUCUGCUCAUUGAUUGAUGGGCAUUUGGGUUGAUUCCACUUUUUGCAAUUGCAAAUUGUGCUGCUAUAAACAUAUGUGUGCAAGUAUCUCUAUCUCUUAUGUAUAAUGACUUCUUUUCCUCUGGGCAGAUACCCAGUAAUAGGGCUGCGGGAUUACUGACAUUCUUUUACAUGCAACAUCCCUAAAACCCAACAAGACGUGUAAACACUGAAGUCCAAGUCUGAUAAUUAUUCUUUCAUUUAAGAAGAACACAUGGGAGUUUCACAUAUUAUUUUUAAAAACUAAUUUUGUAAUAUGUUAAAUGGUAGGACACAUUCAAUUUUUUUUCCUCAUUGGAGAUCUGUCCAUGUUCUGUCUCAAUUUAAUAGCUACCUGGCAUGUAACUGAUGCCUCUGAGCCUACCUCUGGAGUGAAUAAAUAAACGUGGUCCAGGUGAUUUGAUUUCUGCCAUUUGUAGUGGAGAAGUAAAUCUCAGUGAAGAAGAUUUUUUUUCAUAUUUCUUCUUUUUUCUUUUUCUUUUGGCUUCUAUCCUCCUGCUUCCAUGGGACUGACAAUCCAGCUUCUCAAACUCCACGAAAGUCUUAAUACAAGGUGAAUCCCAGAGCCACAAACAGUUUGGACUUCAAACAGUGAGAAAAUUGGACCGAAUGAUUCGGCACACAAAGCAGAAAACUUUCAUUUCCUGUAGGCAGGAUGGAAUUGACUGUUAUAUUAAGACUUCUGAAGAAGCCCUGCCCUGGAGUAAUUUCAGUGCUGUCAGACGAUGUUGACAUCUAGAUUAACCUCUGUGCAGUGAAUUUUACUGCAAAGCUCAUUGAGAUGCAUGUGAUGUGUCUCCACAAAUCCCAUCUGGAACCCGUGGUGGCCCACCCUCAGCAACCCUCCUCUCCCCACUGACUCUGCUUUCUCUGUCCAUAAACUUUUAGCCUCCAGGAGCAGAGGAGCCGUGGCUGAGAUCUGACCCUAGGAGAGGGAGUUUGGGCCUUCUCUGACCAUGAUGCUGAGCCAGGCUUUCUGCUUAGAGUGACAGAGAUUGUCAUUGUAUUGGGUUUCCCCUGAGGGAACUGCAAAUUAAGGCAUGAAAAACACUCUGCUGAUGACAGUUUCACAGCAUAUCUUAAUGCUGCACAAAGUGAAAUGGUUUAAAAGGAAUUAGUGUGUCCUAAGUCAUUGAGCCCUGCUCUGGGCUCUGCAAUCCUCUAGGGAUUCAAGAUCCCAUUGCAACAAGGUCAUGACUGCGUCUAGGCCGGACAGACGGAUUCUGAAGGACAAGGUGUUUGUCUUUUGUGCAGGUCUUUCCUAUGGUCCUUACAAGAGAGGCAGCCACAGCUCCUGUUUCUCCCAACUGGGACAAAAGAUGUAGCUGUUUUCUAAGCACUGGUUUGUCAUCUCUUUAAGGAGUGGUUGGCUCCAGAAUGAGCCAGACUCACUCUAUAAUUCCACAUUGUGGCACAACAGCCACAUAGAACCUCAAAGCUGAAAUUGCAACUUUUCUGCAAAAUAGGGCCAUUGAUUACAUCCAAAGUUUUGAGAAAAGGCCUUCAGGUUAGAUUCAGUCACCUUCAGACUCCACAGAGUUGCUCAGCAUGGUUGCAGGCGUCUUUGGAAACUUACCUCAGGGUUUUAGAAUACGUUACCCUGAAGUCUGGAUAACAAUUUUCUCUGAGAUUUUACUGAUUCUAAUUCCCUUUGAAAUUGUUUUUCCUACUUGCCUCUUGUCUUUCAUUUAAAUAAUAAGAAUCUCCUUGCAUAUUCUUAGGUAUUUCUUUAGGAGAAUUGGAAGUUUCCAGCCAAGGACACUGUGUUUAUGAAUUGGAAAGAUAUCUUUCUGGGCUGAAAAAGGUAAAAAUCAUACGGAGGCAAUCUUGAUGACUUUAUUUAAAAGCAAUUAUCAGCAUUGUGUUUUAUUCUAGGUGCUCGUGCUCAUAGUGCAAACUACAUUCACGUUUUUAAUUAUUUAUGUUAUGAUACUUAUUCGUGUGUACAUAUAUGCGCACACACACACACAAAAGCCUCCACAAUCCUACUGGUAUACAAAUCCAUAUGCCCCAUUUGUGUCGCUUCCGUUGAUCUUUGUGUGCAUGCAUUUGCAAUGAAGUGUGCAUCACAUGUGUGAUUUCUUAAAGUCAUCUAUAGCUCAUCUUUCCUCUUAUUAUCGACACAUACCCUUUGACUUUCUGCACUUUGGAGCUCAUGAAAUUAAGGCUUUUUCAAGGGAGACUACAUCUUGAGUUUCUUUAAACCUUCAUAUUUAAAGAUAGGACUGGUUUUCUUCGAGAAACAAAAACUUGAUUCAGAUUUUAUUUAAUUAAUUAAUUUUCUGGGGGAAAUGGUACUGAAUUUGUUCCUGAGUAACAAAUAGUAGUAAGUGCAAAUAUAAAUGUGAAGUAGUUUAAGCAGGUUAUUGAACCUAUCUUGUGGCUGAAACAAGUAGUCAGAUAUGAAGCUCAGACACUCAAAUUGAAUUAGAACGUGAACCAAAACGGUUAGCAUGGGGCAGGAGAAGAGCACUGGGCUAGGAGCAAGCCUGCUAGAUUGUCACUUGAGUGUCCUUAGCUUAAUGUGGGCAUCUGACAACUAGUUGCAGUCCUGUGCCCCUCUAAUUCCAGAGAUGGGGCAAGCCAAUCUGUUUCUCAUCCAUUGCUCAAGUUGGUUAUCACUGAAAUAUUAUAUACCAUCUCAAGAUCCUGCCCUGAACAAGUUUGCAAACAUCCCCCCCACACUGAGGAGUCAGUCCCAUUUUUGUUUUAUGGCAGUUUAUCUCUUGUGACCCUCCUUUGGAAGCUGUCCAAACUCUGAACACUUGCUGUCCAUUCCCUGCUCCCCACCCCACCCUUUAAGGCCAGGGAAAAGCCAGGGAAAGCCCUAUUGGCUCAUCUCCCUCUUUCCUAGCCUGCACAUCAACCAAGCUUGGGAUUUAGCCUAGGUUUUCAGAGAGGAAAACAAGUGCGUUCUCCCAGCCAUCAGUAUCUUUCCAGCCCCCUGGACCAAGUGAUUAGUGCCUCAUUAGCGCCUCAUCAGUUGCUUUUGCACAAGAGACUCUGGGACAACAAGCCUAUUAUAAUGCCUCAGUCUGUCUUUUUGAAGUCAAACCAUCCUUCUGGCUUGGUUAGGAAAGGGGAGCCUUUCUCCAAACACGUUUUCUUUUAAUUUCCUCUGUUGUUUUCUGGCUGUUAACUAUAUGGAUAAAUGGUAAAACAUAAUUUUCAUUUUUUCUAGGCCCCUAUGAGAGUGGAUAUGCUAUAUUUCUAUAGAUGAGGAGUUCCACAUGUCAGCAAAGCAUUUAUUUAUUUAGUGAAGUGACUAUAAUAUUGACACACAGAUUUGCAGCAGCAUCCAAAUCUUGAGGGGGAAAAAAAAGCCUUUUUCAAUCAAAUGAAACCUUUUCUGUGAUGGCACCAGAGAGGUUUAUAUCUUAAGCACAGAACUGAACCUGAUAAUAUGCUUCCUUUCUAGAAACAAAGAGAUAGAAGAAAUUGCUGAAGGAGCUGGAAGACCAAACCAUCUAUUCCCCAAAUCAUUAUGUAUCAAUAGAUACUUCAACUCUGUUCCUUAAAUGGCUCUGAAAAACACAAAUAACCAUAUUUACUAUUAAAAACAAAUUCAUAAUGUCUAACCCAAUCCCUUAUUUUAAUAUAUAUACAUAUUAAAAUAAUCCCAUGUAUAUAUGAUUAUUAUUAUAUGGGAUAUAUAUAGUUUACAUAUAUAUAGGGGUGUGUGUGUAUAUAUAUAUAUAUAUUUACAUAUAUAUGUAAAUGUAUACUUUUUAAUGCUGGGGAUAGUUCCAUAUUGUUUCUUUUCUUGAUUCCUUCUAAUAUAUUCAAUGAGAUUUAUAAUUUUUUUCACUUUUAUUUCUUUAGGAAAGAGUUGGGGUCUAUUAUGAAUGCUUUCUAGGAUAAAAUGGCAAAACAGAUGGAAAGUGUGGUAGAGGGAGGAUAAUGGGAAUAGGAGGCAGAGAACUUGCACAUUUCUAUUUCCUGCUGAGAGAUCUUGGAAAAACAUUGUCUGCCCUUUACCUCAGUUUCUUAACAUACAAAAUAGAACUACUAUCAACCCCCUGCAUGCCACAGAGGGUUAUUUGAGCCCUAAAUGAGAUCAUAACUGUUAACAUACUCUGUGAACUGUACAGGGCCAGACAAAUAGAGCCCACUCUCUGGGCAGUUGCAUACAGUCUUGCUGGGUGCUGAGCUGAGUGACUGAGAGCCGCUUUUGAGACACAUUUUGAGGCAUAUCUUCCCUAAAUUUUUGCUGGUGUCUGUUUUUUAGAAGUUUUGCCAUUAGCAUUUUUUGCUUUGAGUAUCUAGUGAUGGAGAAUGCUCUAAAAAAUACAAGGAGACAGGGGGAUUCUUUAUCUAUUUGGCUUAGUCACUGGAAAGGGACAAUUAGAGUUUGUUUUCAGGCUUGGAACUCUGACAUUUUGUAGCAAAAUGGCAUCUUCUGCUGCAUUUAAUUCCUUGCCAUCAACUCUUGCUUUCAUAAGGUUCUGUCAAUUUCAACAUAAUGCUUUGUAAAAAUAGGACUCUGUGAAACUUUCUCUAUAAAUUUGGUGGUAUAACUAAUUUUUCAGGGAGCAUCUGAAGGGAUAAUGAUUUUUAAGUGGUACCCUGUUCAUGCCAGGACCAGCAUUUGUACAUGGGAAAAUAAUCUUAAGAUGAGUGAAGAGCAAAUGCUAGACCACACCUUUAAUAGGCCCAAGUGCCAACAAAAAUACGUGUGAGUGGGAUUCCCACGGAGAAAUGUUUCUGAAUGAAAAUGAAACCCUUGAUAAUGAAUCCUGAGGCCAGAAUGCCAAAGUCACAGUAUUCUGUCAUUUACAGCCCCUAAAAAAUCCCAGGUGUUUGUGAUGACAAGCCACUAUUAUAAGUACUCUGUAUUAGUGACUACUUGGCAAGUAAAAUUUUCUCAAAUGUUAUUUUUCAUAGAUCUCCAAGCAACAAUCACUUGCAGUGUAUCUGACAAAAUGCUAUACAUGAUUUUCUAAAAGUAUUUUGAUCACUCCAGAAAGAAAUCAGAAUAAAGCUGCAUACCCCAAAUCCUAGAAAAUUCACAAAUAUUUUGCUCAAGUUCAGGCUCUCUCAGCUUCUCUUUUCUCUUUAACUUUUGCCUCAUACAGAGGCAAUCUUGAUGACAAAAGAUUGGGCUCAAUUUUUGUUUUUCUUGUGUAGAAAAGCAACACCUCUGUUUCGGACUACUGUUCAGUAGACAAAAAGCAUCCCAGCUUUCGAAAUGAGAGUCCAAAUUGGGUUACCACUGAGAUUUUAAAUUAUGAUGUGAAAUUGGAGAAGGUGAACUGUACAGGGCCAGACAAAUAAUAGAGCCCACUCUCUGGGCAGUUGCAUGCAGUCUUGCUGGGUGCUGAGCUGAGAGACUGAGAGCCGCUUUUGAGACGUGUUUUGAGGCAUAUCUUCCUUAAAUUUUUGCUGGUGUCUGUUUUUUAGAAGUUUUGCCAUUAGCAUUUUUCACUUUGAGUAUCUAGCCAUGGAGAAUGCUCUAAAAAAUACAAGGAGACAGGGGGAUGCUUUAUCUAUUUGGCUUAGUCACUGGUUCAGGGUGAAGUUUCAUAAUUUAUUCUGAUAAUCUGGAGGGGAUGACCUCCUUCACAGUACUGUUAAAGCCUUCCUUGAACAAGCUCAUUUCACUAUAUAACUUCCUAAAGACAAGGCUGAUUAUUUAAGGAUUUCAGAGAUAUCAUUUGGGGAAUAACUCACCAGGUAGAGAAAGUUUGACCUGAUAUGUUAACAGGCACAACAAGAACUUAUUUCAAUGCUUUCUCACCAUCUGCCCCUUCUCUGAGAGUUUAGCCUUUCUUAGGAUACUUCCUUUUCCAGGCUAGAAAAGAUUGAUUGUAUUCAUAUCCCAAAGUAAAGGCUCCUCCAAUUCUAUCAGAUGUGGAGGCAACAGAAAAUGACUCAUGUUAUUUUUCUCUCACUUCACAGCAUCAAGAACUCUUCUUGUUUAUGUGGGGGCCAUGGUGGAUUAGCUUGAGGAACUGUCAAAUUAAAAUGAAAGGAAAGCAAGUUGGGGCAAGAAAAUUCUCACUCUGAAUGUGAAAGAAAAUAGCAGUGUUCUUCUCUCUGGCAAAGAUUUGUGUACUGUUGGGGGAAGAUUCAUGUUAUUUCUCAGGUAGACUUUACUUUUUGAGAUUCUGUGUGUGUGUGUGUGUGUGUGUGUGUAUGUGUGUGUGUGUGUGUGUAUUUUGCCUGGUGGGGGGUUAAAGGCAGAUAGAAUGUAGUUGUUUAUGAGUUUAUACUUUCUCUUUAGCAUAAUAGAUGCCCUGUUUAUUUUCUCAGAAUGUGACAAUAAAAUUAGGAAAGGAGAGGAAUUCAGAGGCCCAUGUUGCAGUUCAUGGCAAAGUUUUACCCAAAUAUUUCCUUCAGAAACAUUUAGUCAUAGCAAGCCAUAUAAAUUAUUGUCUGCAACUGGUAUCAGAAAAAGAAAUCAGUAGGUGGGGACUGUAGACCCCAAUGGUGCAUCUGUUUACAAUCUUUCUUUUCCAAGGUUUUAAGGUUCAUGAAUAACAUGAGGGAAUUUUGGGAGAGCUACCACAUCAGUACUUUGGCACGCAUUAACUGUUCCACAGGAAAACUAGGGUUGCUUCAGGGCUAUUUUUGUUUGAAAUGACACACAUACAAAAAAAAAAAAAGACUUUUGGAACAUGUUUUGAGGCCUGUCACCUGAAAUCAGCCUUUGCUGAAAGAGUAUUUAGUUUGAUAAGCGGGAUUUCUUGCUUCUCGCAUCCCAGAGUGUAAAUUCUGCAGCGAAGCCUGGGUGUAUGUUUUCAGCACCAGGGACAGCAAACAACCCCCUGAAUUGAAGGGGCCCGCUAUCCUGAUUGACCUCCCAGACUAGGAAGGGCAGUUGUUUUGUUUUCCUUUAUUUCCUAUCUACCGGAGCCUCAACUUGGAAGACUUUAUUCUUAAGGUUCUUACAUCUUUCAUUUAUUACCAAGCCUAGCUUAGCUGUCUCUGUCACAUUCUUGACCUCCUAACAAAUGGGUUUGGAGUAACACUCCCAGCUCUCCUGGCUCAGAGAAGUAGAAAGAAACACACUAGACUUCAUUUGAAGGGCAUGCUUUAGAGUAGGCUCCCCCUACACAAGUCUUUAUAACAUACCACUGACUUGUAAACCCCUAAAUGAAGGACUGCUUAUACACAAUCAUUUUCCUUUUAACAUUUCUGCACAUUUCUCACAAUGUACAAGUCUAUGUUUGACUCAGUGUGCAUCUGGAGGCAAUGUUUCACAGCAGUUGAGCAGAAGCUAUGAAGUUUGGGGACAGAAAAGGUCCCAGUGAUGCUGCUGUUAUUCAUUUUGGAGACUCAUUGGGGGCACUUCUCUGAUUCUCAGCAUCCACCCUUCAACCCUGAGUGCUCUUUAACAGCUGUUUUUGCCUUAAACAAUCACAAUAAGAAUGCAAAUGACUCCUUGUGGCAUUCUUCAGGCCAGACUGAAGGGUGUACUGAGAAAACAAGGGUAGCAGAAGCACAUGUUGUCACAUUGCUUUGUGAUUGGCCAGUUUUUAUAUAGCACAAUGACACACAGAUAUCAUCUUAGAGUCAUCAUUGUCUACUCUUAACUAAUUGUCAGCAUCUUCUCCACUCAUGUCAGGAUGAAUCCUGUGUUGGGAAGGCAAGUCAGUCACUGCAGGUUUCAUCAUAAAUAUUGCCUUCUAUCUGACAGAUGUUAGAAAACCUCCAUUUUGAAUGCCUCUGUACCAUCCAAGGCUCUGAAUUUCCCCUAUAUCUUAUCCCUUUCUUUCCAUUCCCUUUCCAUGUUGCUUAUCAUAACAUCCAUAACAUUUAGUGGUGUAAGAAAAUAAGGGGUUUCUUUUAGGAAUAAAUGAGGUGGAAAAAGUAGGACAGAGCCAGAUCUCAGAGGAGCAAGUUCAGUGGAACGAUGAUUUCUAACUUGGGAGUGGGUCUAAGAUGUAGCCAUCCAUUCCUUCCAUUCCUUGUCCUCUUGAGUGAAUCUCAUUCCAGUGCUCACACUUGCCCUGCAAAAAAGGCCAUGGCACAAGAUUCUCUAGAUUAUUUGUAUGAAGACUGGAGGUGAGCAGCAUCCAACACCUCUGUUAGAGUUCUUUAGAAUAGAGGAGUUUUGUCUUAUAUUUUAAUCCAGGAACCUUCCCAUAUUUAAAAAGUUUAGAAAUAAUAUGUACAGAAAGGACCUAUGGGGAUAGGAAAGCUUAAUAAUACAAGUUAUUUUCCCUUAGAACAGAGGGGAAGGAGCUGCAAAGUGACUGCUAAUGGAGGAACGAUCUGCUGGCUGGGGGAAAUGUGGCCUGAGACUAGAGAUGCAGAGCAGGCAUCUCUAGAAGGAGAGAUGAUGCCAAUAGAAGCCCCAGGAGGGAACUGGCCAGCGAAUACAAUUUUAUAAAGAUUCUCAGUACUUUUUCUGAAAAAAUUCCUAAAAUUUUCAAGGGCGCGUCUAGCCCUCUGCCUCUUUAGAGGUGAGCUCAGUGCUACUUCUGGGUUCUUAAGGCAAAUGCCCUACAAACACCAAAGUCUUGUAUUUUCCACUCUCAGCCGGCACUGGCUAAGUGGGAUUUUUUUUUUCCCUUCCCUAAGUGAAAGGGACUUGUUUUCAGGAGAAGUGUCCUUUAAACAUCCAGCUAAAACUGGAAGUAAUUUUUUGCAUGAAUGGCUUUUUACAGCUAGGUCUACAGCAGAACAAAACUUGUAUUAAACUAAGUGCUACUUUACAUAUCUUAUUUCAAGGGAAAUGAAGGAUUUAUUGUCGUGUAAAUGAUAUACACUGAUUUGUUUCCUACUGGACAUUACAUGUCCCUUUAUCUCUAGGCUGAUGUUGUGCAGCAAACUUUCAAUAUCUGGAAAAUCAGCUGGUACCUACUUCAGUGCAUUAUUAGGAUAUUACGUUCCCUGAGAGGAAUUUUGCCAAUGAAGUUUAGGUACUGUUGUAACUGAUUUCCAUCCCCCCUCCCUAAGCUUCUGUACUAAGUAUAUGUAAAGCUAUUAUAUCUUGUCUGAUCCCAUGUGUUCAUGUGUGUUUCCCAAUGUUUGCAUAAAUAUAUUGGCAAUCUGAAGGGUUAGCUGGCUUAUGGCAACUGCUGAACAAUGGUAUGUUUGGCAUGUGGGACACCUGAUACCUGGGCACACCUGUUCUGAGGCCAAGCUAAUUUUACAGAUUUUGGAAAAGAAAAAACAGCAGCAACAACAACAGUGUGGCUUGAAUUAAGGAAAGUUUAACAAUGAAUACAGUAUUGCCAAGUCAUCAUUUAUGGGUGGAGACGUUGACCACAGCAGUUGAGGUGCUUUCAACUGGAUCUUAUGCCCUUUAUUUUAAUCCCAAUUGAUAGUUCCUCAUUUGUAUUUUAUGACUUAGAAAUACUCCUACGUGAUGCUCGUUUGUUUUUCUCCCAGGCUUCUGGAAAGUGCUGAUCAUGAUUGCUUCCUAUCAUUUGGAUCCCAAAGUUGAUAACUUAACAUAAGUGACUGAGGUUUUAGUAGAACUGGGUUUUACUAAUCGUAUCUCCUCCUUGAGGUGCUGUUCCCUUCAUUCCUUUCCUUUAUGACAGGUGAAUGCAUUGGCUAUGCUGAUUUUAUUUGCAUCCUGGCGAGUCUUGGAGAAUCAAUCUCGUUAAAAUGAUGACUGCAUUUGCCUUUGGAGAAGAGGUUUAUUGUCUAAGUAAAACUCUUAUGUGAAGGUGUCAUUUAUGUAAAAAAAAAAAAAAAUUCUAACUUGAUAAGAUGGCCACAGGUUAGAGGGGUGUGUUCUCAGUUGAUAUUAAGGGAUAUGUUGAAAAGGCAAGUGCCCACCCUCUAUUCUUCAUCUCACCCUUCCUUUCUCCCCAACCUCAAAAGAAAACAAAAAAUUAUUUUUUUAAAUUGUAUUAGUAAUUUAUGUUUAAUACAAAAGGAUGAUUUAAUGGUAUCACCAAAGGUUGUUUCUCCCAUUGUGCAUGUCCUUCAGUCUCGGCCCCAUACCCAUCACCCCAUUCUUCACCCUCAUGCUUCCAUCCCAAGGCAAACAUGUGUCUUCAUCGGAAUCUAUGGGUGUUGAAGUUAAAUGUGGGGGCAGAGAUUUAACACCAUGACACUAAUACAAAUCAACCAUUCUUCACUUUCAAAUGGUUAAUCACUACAGGAAGGCGAACUCUUUUCUUGGUUUUUGUUUAAAAACAUUUUAUACAUAUAUAUGUAUAUAUGUGUGUGUAUGUAUGGACAUAGGUAUGUAUAUGCACAUGUACAUGUAUAUAUGUAUAUAUCCAUCUUCAAUAUAAAUAUAUCAUAAGUGAGAGUUGUAAAUACUCCUUGGUCAUAUGUCUGUCUUUCUCAUAGUAUCAUAUCUUCAAUGUUAUGUUAACAACUCCAUUUAUUGAUUGAUGAAAUCGUGUGUAGACCUGUAUCCUCCUGACAUAGUUUAUGUAGGGUCUCUUCUCAAAUAAAGUAUAAAACAACAA